GACAGCUAAUGGCGGCGGCCGCCUGAGGCGGGCGGGCGGUAUAGAGCGGGCGGCAGGAGGCAAGCAGCGAAACCUUCCCGGCCGCCGCUCCCGUCCCGACGGCGGCUUCCCCAAGGCGGCAGGACUCGGCGCGCCAUGGACAGGCCGGCGGCGGCGGCGGCGGCGGGCUGCGAGGGCGGCGGGGGCCCGAACCCGGGGCCGGCGGGCGGCAGGAGGCCUCCUCGGGCCGCGGGGGGCGCCACCGCCGGCUCCCGGCAGCCCAGCGUGGAGACCCUGGACAGUCCCACAGGAUCACAUGUUGAAUGGUGUAAACAGCUUAUAGCUGCUACAAUUUCUAGUCAGAUUUCAGGUUCAGUGACAUCAGAAAAUGUGUCCAGAGAUUACAAGGUUUUCAGGAGGCCUGAUCUAAGGAACAUUCAUAAAGCAAGACAAAGAUUGGAGAUUCAGGAAGAACACAAUGGCUACCCUUCUGAAGCUGAAGCUGAUCAGGCUCUAAGGGAUGGAAAUAAGCUGGCACAGAUGGAAGAGGCUCCACUUUUCCCAGGAGAAUCAAUUAAAGCCAUUGUGAAAGAUGUCAUGUAUAUCUGCCCAUUUAUGGGAGCAGUGAGUGGAACCCUGACAGUGACGGACUUUAAGCUGUACUUCAAAAAUGUCGAGAGGGACCCGCAUUUUAUCCUUGAUGUUCCCCUUGGAGUGAUCAGCAGAGUGGAGAAGAUUGGAGCACAGAGCCAUGGAGACAAUUCCUGUGGUAUAGAGAUAGUGUGCAAGGAUAUGAGGAACUUGCGGCUUGCUUAUAAACAGGAAGAACAGAGUAAACUAGGGAUAUUUGAAAACCUCAACAAACAUGCAUUUCCUCUUUCUAACGGACAGGCACUAUUUGCAUUCAGCUAUAAAGAAAAAUUUCCAAUUAAUGGCUGGAAAGUUUAUGAUCCAGUAUCUGAAUAUAAGAGACAGGGCUUGCCAAAUGAGAGUUGGAAAAUAUCCAAAAUAAACAGUAAUUAUGAGUUCUGUGACACCUACCCUGCCAUCAUUGUUGUGCCAACUAGUGUAAAAGAUGAUGACCUUUCAAAAGUGGCAGCUUUUCGAGCAAAAGGCAGAGUCCCUGUGUUGUCAUGGAUUCAUCCGGAAAGUCAAGCAACGAUUACCCGUUGCAGCCAGCCACUUGUGGGUCCCAAUGAUAAGCGCUGCAAAGAGGAUGAAAAAUACUUGCAAACAAUAAUGGAUGCUAACGCACAGUCACACAAGCUUAUCAUCUUUGAUGCUCGACAAAACAGUGUCGCUGAUACCAACAAGACAAAGGGUGGAGGAUAUGAAAGUGAAAGUGCUUACCCAAAUGCAGAACUUGUGUUCUUGGAGAUCCACAACAUUCAUGUCAUGCGAGAGUCACUACGCAAAUUAAAAGAGAUUGUGUACCCUUCGAUCGAUGAGGCGCGGUGGCUCUCCAAUGUGGAUGGGACGCAUUGGCUGGAAUAUAUAAGGAUGCUGCUUGCUGGGGCAGUAAGAAUUGCUGAUAAAAUAGAAUCUGGGAAAACAUCUGUGGUGGUGCAUUGCAGCGACGGUUGGGACCGAACAGCCCAGCUCACAUCUCUGGCUAUGCUAAUGUUGGACAGUUACUACAGGACCAUUAAAGGAUUUGAAACUCUCGUAGAAAAGGAGUGGAUAAGCUUUGGACACAGGUUUGCACUGCGAGUGGGCCAUGGUAAUGACAACCAUGCGGAUGCUGACCGAUCUCCCAUAUUUCUGCAGUUUGUUGAUUGUGUUUGGCAAAUGACAAGGCAGUUUCCUUCAGCAUUCGAGUUUAAUGAGCUAUUCUUGAUUACAAUUUUGGAUCACCUUUAUAGCUGUCUUUUUGGGACCUUUUUGUGCAACUGUGAACAGCAGCGAUUCAAAGAGGAUGUAUAUACAAAGACGAUAUCUUUAUGGUCGUAUAUCAAUAGCCAGCUAGACGAGUUUUCUAAUCCCUUCUUUGUGAAUUAUGAAAACCACGUGUUAUAUCCUGUUGCUAGUCUGAGUCAUUUGGAAUUGUGGGUAAAUUAUUAUGUACGAUGGAAUCCACGGAUGAGACCUCAGAUGCCCAUUCACCAGAAUCUCAAGGAGCUGCUGGCCGUCAGGGCGGAGCUGCAGAAGCGUGUGGAGGGCCUACAGCGGGAGGUGGCCACGCGCGCCGUCUCAUCCUCAUCUGAGCGGGGCUCCUCGCCCUCCCACUCCGCCACCUCCGUCCACACCUCGGUCUGAUGGGCGAGGUCAGCCUGCUGCUCCACUGUCUCCCGGUGGCUCAGGAAAGGGACCUGGCGAUCACUGUUAUGGCUGUAGCUUGUGAUCUUGUCUUUUAGGAUUAGGCCCAGGGACCAUUUGUGUGGCUAGGUGACAGCUCCCACUGUUGGCAACCGUUACCCUCCUGUCAGCGGUUUCACAGGGGAGCCGUCUGUCACGCCCACCCUGUGAAGCAACUUCUGGCAUUCAGGCAGCUUGGGAGAAACUAAGUGAACGGAAUGCAGUACUGAGGUUCAAGAAAGCUGUACGCCAUUUCUUUCCAACUUAAAUCCUUCAGUAACAACAAACACCACUCACUUCAAGAUGCAUUGCCAGCCCCGUGGCUUCCCUCAGCUCUUGGCCACAACUUGAAAACUGUCUUGAAUGAAGUACUUGGGGAGAAGACAGGCCACUGCCCUCUGUUCCACAGUUUUCUUCAUGCACGGGGUCCUCCUGUUAACAAUUACUGUUGUGUACAUAUAAGGUAUUUUUAGAGAAGAGAAACAGGCCUUUAUUUUCCUAUGUCCUUUUUUACGUUUAGAAUAGUCACCCGAGGGGGGAUCAGCUCAACUGUACUGUGGGAGAAAUUCUUUUCCAACAAACCUCAUGCUCGUUUUUCUGUGGUGCAAUUUCAAGGGCAACGUGUUCUGUCCUCACCUCACUCUGGUACUCGCCUCUUGGGGCGGCUCAGCCCAUUCAUGGGGAUGGCACCAAGCGGCCAUGCUCAGUCUUCCAGCCCCGCUGAGGGUAAACCGAGGCCUCUGGCAGCUGUGCACAGGUGCUGGCCUCUGGCUCCUUCAAGGAGCACUGCCUGUCACUCGCUCCUGGGCUGUCUAGCCAUGUCUCCCACCCCCACUUUACCGCAGCCAGCUGCUGGGAUCAAAGCAAGUCUGUUCUUAUGUUAUUUGCCUGUAUGAAAUCAUUUCUCAUUUUAUCACAAUUCCUUCAACUCAGCUUACUCGCGUGGCUGCCUGUUCAUAUUUGAAAGCAGCCACCGUGCUGUGGCUUUGGUUUGGAAAAGCAUAGCACGCACUUCCCUUGGUUUUCCCUUCCCAGAGCCGACCGCAGCUGGUCAGCCCUCUCUUCCCGCUCCUGAACCUUUACUUACUGACUUUGAGCUCUGUGACUCCGUCGGUUCUCGCAGGAAUUAACUAACUUACCAAUUGGUUCAAUCCACUUGAGCGCCAUAGCUCUGAGCUCCUCUGUGUGACAUGCCACAGAUGACUAUUGCACACCUGGGUCCUGCCCCAGCAGGCCAUGCCCCUCCCAUGUGCCGUGCCUGUUGCUGCAGCUGCCCCCCCACCCCGCCACUGGCUGCAGGAAUUCAGCCUUUAGAGGCAGAGGCAGCUGCAGCGGCCCCUGAGGUCAAACCCCAGUGUGACUGCAUAGCAGUGUUAGCUGGUUGGUUUCAAACUACUGGAUUCCAGGCAAAGGCCUACAGAUUGACCUUAUUAUUUUUGAAAAUAUGUUAAGGGUUUUUUCGUAGAGAGAGAAAGAAUGGAUUUUUUUUUAACUGGGAACCUCCUGAUUCUUACGGAAAAUUAUCCUUCUAUAAGAAGAUACCAGAGAGAUUUAUUCAAGGUAAUUUGAUAACCUAAAAUCAAUUCUCCAUUUUUUAUCAUAUGUGGGAUUUGUUGCUAAGUCGUGUUCAACAAUAGCUUUUAUGUUCCUAACAUAUCUGAAAGCUUAUUUAUGAAUGGAUAUACUGGAUUAUUGAUAUACUGAUUUUUUUUUUAAUGGGGACAUUUGCCAUUUUCUUCCCAGAAAUAUGUAAUCCCCUGGCUGACUAGGACUGUUAAACAUAGUGUGGACUGGAUGAUGCCUUCGACAAACCAGAGAAGCCAAGUUGGGGGGAGCUGGUGCCUGGAGUGGGCCCUGUGCACCUCACCUGGCGGAGGCUGGGGGGGGCUCUGUCAGCAGGACCCUAGAGGAGACUCUCAUUCGAUUUUAAAGAAGCACAACGGGUCAUUUUCCUUUGUAUGUUCCUAGCGCAGAACUGUUUCUAAAACAACUUGAAGUAUAGUUUUGUUAUCUAAGCAAUUUUUGUUUUAAGUAAGUAAGUGUACUAGAAUGCGAAGCCGUUAUGGUUCAGGUUUUUAAAAACUGGUACAGUAUUGUAUUUGUCUCAUCUGUUGCACUGUAUUUCAAUCAUCUGUAAUUAAAAUGAUCAUAUGUUUGCUCCCUGGUCUUUUUUAAGUAAGUAAGUAAGUAUCUUAGUAGAUUUUUCCUUUGAGGAAAAUCGGUAAUAAAAUAACAUGGAUUGAAUGUUUACUGUGCGUCAAGCACAGUUAAUAUAUGAUGAUGUAAAGUAACUAACUUUAUGUGAUUUAAUUCAUUCAGUAAAUUGUAAAUGUAUCAUGA